ACCCUUCCAGCGUCGCCUCGGGGACUCGCACCCCUUUCCCUGGCCGCACAAGACGUUUCAUCCUUGGCGGCCGCCGCCAACCCGCCGGGAGGGGCGGUCGGAACUGGCAGGCCGGGGCGGAACCCCCGGGGUCUCCUUGUCGAGGCCCGGGCAGCCAGAUCCUCAGGGCCGGUCCGGGCGGGAGCCCGGUCGAUGGAGGCGGCUCCCGUCCUCAGCUCCCGCUCCCUCCCCUUCCCCGGGGCGGGCGCGCGCGGGCCGGGAGCUGGGAGGCGGCGGCUCCCGCCCGGGAGGCGGUGGCGAGGGCGGCGGAGGCGCGGCCGGGCGGGUCCCAGGGCCGUGGUUCUCCAGCGCAGGAGUCCCCGGCGCACCCGCUGCGCUCGCCCCGCAGCCGCAGCCUGAGCGGCCGAAGUCGCCACCAGCUGUGUCCGCGCAGAUCCCGGGCGCGGAGGGGAGAGGUCGCCCGCUUGUCGCCCCCGCCGGACCCCGGGCACCGCGUAGCACCCAAGCGCCACCCGGACGAGGGGCCCUGGGGAGCGGCUGAGGCCGAAGACCCGAGGGAAGGAGGAGCCCGCGGACGGCUGCAGCCCCAGACUGUAUUUUCUGUGAGUCCUGAUCAAGUGAUACAAAUGAGCUGCAAUGGUGACAUAAACUCUUGACAGAGAUUGGAAAAGUAGCUGGAACACCAUCUUUUCUUUUAACUUUUUAUGGUGCUUCUGUUGGCAUAGUUGGGGAAAGCACCUACAACAUGAGUUUUAUCAUGAAGCUUCACAGACACUUUCAAAGAACAGUCAUUCUGCUUGCCACUUUUUGUAUGGUGAGCAUUAUCAUUUCUGCUUACUACCUGUACAGUGGCUACAAACAGGAAAAUGAACUCUCUGAGACGGCUUCAGAAGUUGACUGUGGCGACCUCCAACACCUACCAUAUCAACUAAUGGAAGUGAAAGCAAUGAAGCUUUUUGAUGCCUCAAGGACAGACCCCACAGUCCUAGUAUUUGUAGAGAGCCAGUACUCAUCUCUUGGUCAAGACAUCAUUAUGAUUCUAGAAUCAAGUAGAUUCCAGUAUCACAUUGAAAUUGCCCCUGGAAAGGGAGAUCUCCCAGUGCUUAUAGACAAAAUGAAAGGCAAAUACAUUCUCAUUAUUUAUGAGAAUAUUUUAAAGUAUAUAAAUAUGGAUUCCUGGAAUCGAAGCCUUCUAGAUAAAUACUGUGUAGAAUAUGGUGUGGGUGUCAUUGGAUUCCACAAAACUAGUGAGAAGAGUGUACAGAGCUUUCAGUUAAAAGGUUUCCCUUUUUCCAUAUAUGGAAAUCUUGCAGUAAAAGAUUGUUGUAUUAAUCCUCAUUCUCCAUUGAUUCGUGUGACCAAAUCUUCCAAGCUUGAAAAAGGUUCUUUACCUGGAACUGACUGGACAGUUUUUCAGAUUAAUCAUUCAGCCUAUCAACCAGUAAUAUUUGCCAAAGUAAAGACCCCAGAAAACCUUUCUCCUUCCAUCUCUAAAGGUGCUUUUUAUGCCACUAUUAUACAUGACCUGGGGCUUCAUGAUGGAAUUCAAAGGGUUCUUUUUGGCAACAACUUGAACUUUUGGCUGCACAAGCUCAUCUUCAUAGAUGCCAUCUCCUUCUUAUCAGGGAAGAGGCUGACAUUGUCCUUGGACAGGUACAUUCUUGUGGAUAUUGAUGAUAUAUUUGUGGGAAAAGAGGGAACAAGAAUGAACACCAAUGAUGUAAAGGCCCUGCUUGAUACUCAGAAUCUUUUGCGUGCACAAAUCACAAAUUUUACAUUCAACCUGGGAUUUUCAGGGAAAUUUUACCAUACAGGAACUGAAGAGGAAGAUGAAGGAGAUGACUGUCUGUUGGGGUCUGUGGAUGAGUUCUGGUGGUUUCCUCACAUGUGGAGCCAUAUGCAGCCCCACCUCUUCCACAAUGAGUCAUCUUUGGUGGAGCAGAUGAUUCUCAACAAAAAAUUUGCCUUAGAGCACGGCAUUCCAACGGACAUGGGCUACGCUGUGGCCCCUCACCAUUCGGGCGUCUACCCUGUACAUGUUCAGCUUUAUGAGGCCUGGAAGAAGGUCUGGAAUAUUAAAAUCACCAGCACUGAAGAAUAUCCACAUCUGAAGCCAGCUAGAUACCGGAGGGGUUUUAUCCACAAAAACAUCAUGGUUCUCCCAAGACAAACCUGUGGGCUUUUCACUCACACCAUUUUCUACAAAGAAUAUCCAGGGGGUCCUAAAGAGCUGGAUAAGAGUAUCCAAGGAGGAGAACUUUUCUUCACUGUCGUCCUCAACCCUAAAAUGAGAUAGAAGAAAGAGUAACUCAUCUUUGGACAAAACCUGCUCGUGUAUUCAAAAAUGGGGAUAGUUUGGAGGAAUGUGAUAUUUGGACUUUUGAAAGUUUAUCAACCUUCAGAUCCCAAAAAUACAAAUAAGUCUGGUUUGAACAUCAGAAAUAUAAUAACUCUUCUAACUUACCUAUUUUCACAAAUGGAAGUAUUUUGAGUCUCCUUAUACAGCUUUCUUCUCUUUUUUCUCAAUUCAGCCAGUACAGUAAUAUACAGUCAAAAAGAGUUAAACCAAUGCCUGGUUAUGAACUGAAGAAGCAGUUAAAACACUCUUAAAAUGCUAACAUUUUCACCAAUAAUUUUAAGCACUUUAAUCUAUCAUCUGUAAAAUUCUGAUGUUUCACAUUUACUUUCAUCAUAGAGCAACAGAAGUAUUAACAAAUAAUCAUGAACUUCUUAAAAGUUCACAGUAGGAUUUUAUCUCCGAAUUUCUAAACCAAAUGAGUUUCAUUUAGUGUGGAAGAAAUUCAAAGUUAAAUCAUUCAUGUACAAUGGAUUUAUACUAAGAAUUUCAUCCAUUUUGUGAUAAGAAAUAUUACAUUUUUUAUUAAUUUAAAAACCAAACUAUUGUCUUUGUUUUUAAAAACCUUACAGUAAAGUUUAUGUUAAUCUUGGACACUAAUUGGACUAACUGAGCAAAUUCCUUAACAAACCUCGCUAUUUUUCAGGCCUUUAUGAAUGAUAUUUGGCAAUUUUAUGUCUUGAGGAGGAGAUUCAUAAGAAUAAAGGUGGCAGGUUGGGGGAGCCGCACAAAACUUGUUCUUUCCUGAUUCAGAAAACUUUCAGUAGACAAUUACUUUCAGAAAAAAAUCCCUAGACUCAAAAUAAAUGACAAAUCUUGUCAGAUGCCACAAGACAGACAAGGAACCCAAAGCUAACGUUAUCUGGCACACCAACUCUAAUACUGGAAGCAAUUCUACUCACCUGGAAACAAAAGGUUAAGAAGCCCACAUCUGGAUUCAGCCCACAUCUAGCCGGAGGCCGGACUACUAUAAUUAGUUAGUGAUGUCUGUCUUGGAGAACAGAGUAAGGAGUAGUGGCAUGUUUCCCAUGAAUUCUCCAUCCUGAAAUUAAGUGCUUGGACAAAGUUUGUAUUGAAACUAAGGAAGAUCCAGAUGCAGUAAGGCAUGCCAGUAAUUUAGCAGAUGACAUUUUUUAUUAGGCCAGGAUGGAAAUGAGAAAACCUUGAUGGAAUCAAAGUAUACAUUAGCUGCAGGAAAGUCAUGAAUUUUAAUUAUAGUGGAUUUGAAAGAUAGCCAUUGUAAGUUUAAGUAAUACCCCAGGCCUCAAUUAGAAGUGCCAUUUUCUGAGAAUGCCAAGUGAGGUUAUCGUUUACUACAAAAAGAUAGAUGUGUAUUGGAAACAUGGCACUUAAAUACAUUCACAUACAUUUGAGCUGAAAACAAAAAUAUAAACAGGACUUUAAUUAAUGAGGGUUUUAAGUUUUUCCCAUAUGUCAACAUAAUAUCAAGGUGCUAUACUAACUUACCAGUACUGGGGUGAGAAAGGGUUACAAUAAGGUGCCCCUCAGAGUUAAACUGGAAAGAUCACAGCAAAGGUAAAAAAACCGUUAAACAGAAUAACUCUCUGGCCUGAAAUGUUCUAAUGUUACCAAAAUAUUUGUCAUGUAAAAGAAAGAAGUAUCAAUCAAGUGAAUUUAACAAAAUAGAGAAUUACAAAGACAAAUGUUAGCACUGUCUGGGGAAGAGAAAACUUUGGUCAUCUCUAAAUGAGCUUUUCCAAUGUCACAGGCCUGGACAACUCUCACGUAAGCUGGAUGCAGGGGUUUUGAUUAAUAGACUUUGAAGUUUAGAUCCAUUUGGGGGAGGUGGACCUAGCAGGCUAUCUGAGCCUGGAACCAUUGAGAUUUCCAUUUUUCUAAUACUACUUUUCCUGAUUCUAAACCCAACUGAUGACUUCCUCAUUAUGGUUUACUUUCCCACGUAGAUCCUACUAUAGGAAAAGAAUAUGUUAAUCAUAGGAACUUGUACUCUCUGGGACAAUAAUUUGCAAUAUAAUUUUAUAAGUUUUAUUUUAAUUGAUCAAUACUUCCCAUGUAACCGGACUACCUGGAAAGAGCCCUCUAAUUGUAUAGACAGUAAUUGAAGAGUAUUUCAGUUCCUCUCUAAUUUAUAAUUACCCAUUUUAAACUAAUAGAUGGUAUCCUGCUUUUAUUCAUUGGUUUCAUGAGCUUUUGCUAAUCUGAUUCUGCCCCAGAAAAAUACUGACUCUCUCUGCAAGUGUACUGAAUCAGGUUUUGGAGCCUGUCGGUCAGAAACAGACCUCAGAGUGUUCGUUGAUUAAGGAUGGUAAUGAGAGUUACCUCAUGAUAUACCAUGGGAGAGAGCCACUGGAAGUACCCCAGAGUCACUGCUAGCAACACACAGGCAUGAGAUUUCUACACAAACAUGUAAUAUACCUAGAUACAAACAUUCUUGAUCAAUUUACAAUUAUACAGAGUACUCAUAUAUAUUUUCAAAAAUUGUGAUAUUCUAUUUACUUUAGAUACUUAUAUAAAAUAAAAUGCAGAAGGGUACUAAGAACUGAAACUUAUGAAGAUAACAAAAAGGAUUAAUUGGCAAUGACUGCAUCUGCCCUCAAUAAAUAAAACUCUAUAUAUGACGUAUAUACUUAGACAAAAGGAACUAGUACGACUAUAGUGUUCAUUUUAACAAGUUUCCAGUUCCACCUAUCUUAGGAAGAUGCAGUAAUAGUUAAUUAAUAUGCUGAUUGGAAAAGUUCCGGCUUAGACAGGUUUGUACUUCUUGUGGGAGCCAUAUUAUCAUCUCAUAUGCACUAAACAAAAAUGUCACUUUUUUGCUUCAGGGUUCUUAUCUCUAAUCACAAGAUGUUAUGAGUCUUUGCUUAUGCACUUGUUGAAUAAAUAGACUCCAGGUAUUGAGUCAUUAACAACUAUAGAUAUAGAACACUUUGCCUCCCUUCAACAUGCUUGAUAAUAAAGUCAGUGCUUACCUAUUAAUCCAAAAAAGCAGCUGUGGAUUGCCACAAGAUUCAUGCCAAUGGGCCAGGCGCAGUGGCUCACGCCUGUAAUGUCAGCACUUUGGGAGGCCAAGGUGGGCAGAUCAUGAGGUCAGGAGAUCAAGACCAUCCUGGCUAACACGGUGAAACCCUGUCUCUACUAAAAAUACAAAAAAUUAGCCAGGCGUGGUGGCAGGCGCCUGUAGUCCCAGCUACUCAGGAGGCUGAGGUAGGAGAAUCACUGGAAUCCAGGAGGCAGAGGUUGCAGUGAGCCAAGAUCACGCCACUGCACUCCAGCCUGGGCGACAGAGCGAGACUCUGUCUCAAAAAAAAUGCGCGCCAAUACUACACUUGCUUGGAAUUCAGGUGAAGCAAAUCCCUGACCAUGUAACAAUAUUGUGCCUCCUUCAUCAAACCAUUAACCAUCCCACAGAACCAUUAGCUAACCCCUUUAUGCACGCAUUUUAUUAAAUGCUUUUUGUCUCUCUGUUUCUCAAUUUGAUAUAGCAUACUUCCACCAUACCCUACAUACCCUCCUACUCAAAUCCCUAAAAGUUAAAUCUAAAUUGUGUUUCUCUUAUUAUAAACAUGGAUGUGAAUAGAGUGAAUAUCUUAAACUAGGAUUAACACAUAGAUUGAUUACAACUAAAAUAAAUAAAACAGAAUUCACUCAAGAAGAAAGCCUUUAUAAAAAGAAAUUAACCCACAUUGAAAUUGAAAAAAAAUACUGUAAUUUUAUAUGUGUAUGUGCUUUUCUCUAAAAUUCAUCUGAAAGGAAAUAAUACAUUGACCUAAUGGGAAGUUUUAUGUUUCUUUUUUUGUUCGCUAGUUCUGGAACACAUUCUAAUAAUAGGAGACCCUUCGCUGAAAAAUAAAUAAAUGAUAAUAACUUUAGACCUAGAAAAGUAAUUCCUGGUCUAACGUUUAAGUCUUUAAUCCAUCUUGAAUUGAUUUUUGUAUAAGGUGUAAGGAAGGGAUCCAGUUUCAGCUUUCUACAUAUGGCUAGCCAGUUUUCCCAGCACCAUUUAUUAAAUAGGGAAUCCUUUCCCCAUUGCUUGUUUUUCUCAGGUUUGUCAAAGAUCAGAUAGUUGUAGAUAUGCAGCAUUAUUUCUGAGGGCUCUGUUCUGUUCCAUUGAUCUAUAUCUGUGUUUUGGUACCAGUACCAUGCUGUUUUGGUUACUGUAGCCUUGUAGUAUAGUUUGAAGUCAGGCAGCGUGGUUCCUCCAGCUUUGUUCUUUUGGCUUAGGAUUGACUUGGCGAUGCGGGCUCUUUUUUGGUUCCAUAUGAACUUUAAAGUAGUUUUUUCCAAUUCUGUGAAGAAAGUCAUUGGUAGCUUGAUGGGGAUGACAUUGAAUCUCUAAAUUACCUUGGGCAGUAUGGCCAUUUUCACGAUAUUGAUUCUUCCUACCCAAGAGCAUGGAAUGUUCUUCCAUUUGUUUGUAUCCUCUUUUAUUUCCUUGAGCAGUGGUUUGUAGUUCUCCUUGAAGAGGUCCUUCACAUCCCUUGUAAGUUGGAUUCCGAGGUAUUUUAUUCUCUUUGAAGCAAUUGUGAAUGGGAGUUCACUCAUGAUUUGGCUCUCUGUUUGUCUGUUGUUGGUGUAUAAGAAUGCUUGUGAUUUUUGUACAUUGAUUUUGUAUCCUGAGACUUUGCUGAAGUUGCUUAUCAACUUAAGGAGAUUUUGGGCUGAGACAAUGGGGUUUUCUAGAUAUACAAUCAUGUCGUCUGCAAACAGGGACAAUUUGACUUCCUCUUUUCCUAAUUGAAUACCCUUUAUUUCCUUCUCCUGCCUAAUUGCCCUGGCCAGAACUUCCAACACUAUGUUGAAUAGGAGUGGUGAAAGAGGGCAUCCCUGUCUUGUGCCAAUUUUUAAAGGGAAUGCUUCCAGUUUUUGCCCAUUCAGUAUGAUAUUGGCUGUGGGUUUGUCAUAGAUAGCUCUUAUUAUUUUGAGAUAUGUCCCAUCAAUACCUAAUUUAUUGAGAGUUUUUAGCAUGAAGGGUUGUUGAAUUUUGUCAAAGGCCUUUUCUGCAUCUAUUGAGAUAAUCAUGUGGUUUUUGUCUUUGGUUCUGUUUAUAUGCUGGAUUACAUUUAUUGAUUUGCGUAUAUUGAACCAGCCUUGCAUCCCAGGGAUGAAGCCCACUUGAUCAUGGUGGAUAAGCUUUUUGAUGUGCUGCUGGAUUUUGUUUGCCAGUAUUUUAUUGAGGAUUUUUGCAUCAAUGUUCAUCAAGGAUAUUGGUCUAAAAUUCUCUUUUUUGGAUGUGUCUCUGCCCGGCUUUGGUAUCAGCAUGAUGCUGGCCUCAUACCAUAAAAACCCUAGAAGAAAACCUAGGCAUUACCAUUCAGGACAUAAGCACGGGCAAGGACUUCAUGUCUAAAACACCAAAAGCAAUGGCAACAAAAGACAAAAUUGACAAAUGGGAUCUAAUUAAACUCAAGAGCUUCUGCACAGCAAAAGAAACUACCAUCAGAGUGAACAAGCAACCUACAAAAUGGGAGAAAAUUUUCACAACCUACUCAUCUGACAAAGGGCUAAUAUCCAGAAUCUACAAUGAACUCAAACAAAUUUACAAGAAAAAAACAAACAACCCCAUCAAAAAGUGGGCGAAGGACAUGAACAGACACUUCUCAAAAGAAGACAUUUAUGCAGCCAAAAAACACAUGAAAAAAUGCUCACCAUCACUGGCCAUCAGAGAAAUGCAAAUCAAAACCACAAUGAGAUACCAUCUCACACCAGUUAGAAUAGCAAUCAUUCAAAAGUCAGGAAACAACAGGUGCUGGAGAGGAUGUGGAGAAAUAGGAACACUUUUACACUGUUGGUGGGACUGUAAACUAGUUCAACCAUUGUGGAAGUCAGUGUGGCAAUUCCUCAAGGAUCUAGAAGUAGAAAUACCAUUUGACCCAGCCAUCCCAUUACUGGGUAUAUACCCAAAGGACUAUAAAUCAUACUGCUAUAAAGACACAUGCACACGUAUGUUUAUUGCAGCAUUAUUCACAAUAGCAAAGACUUGGAACCAACCCAAAUGUCCAACAAUGAUAGACUGGAUUAAGAAAAUGUGGCACAUAUACACCAUGGAAUACUAUGCAGCCAUAAAAAAUGAUGAGUUCAUGUCCUUUGUAGGGACAUGCAUGAAAUUGGAAAUCAUCAUUCUCAGUAAACUAUCGCAAGAACAAAAAACCAAACACCGCAUAUUCUCACUCAUAGGUGGGAACUGAACAAUGAGAACACAUGGACACAGGAAGGGGAACAUUACACUCUGGGGACUGUUGUGGGGUGGAGUGAGAGGGGAGGGAUAGCAUUGGGAGAUAUACCUAAUGCUAGAUGACGAGUUAGUGGGUGCAGCGCACCAGCAUGGUACAUGUAUACAUAUGUAACUAACCUGCAUAUUGUGCACAUGUACCCUAAAACUUAAAGUAUAAUAAUAAUAAAAAAAAGAAAUAUUAAAAAACAACAACAACAACAAAAAUAAAAUAAAAUAAAAGUAAUUCCUGAACAUGCCUAAUAGUGAGUACUGCCUGAGAUGCUUGAAUUUUAGAAAUCAAACUUAAUGCAUCAGAAUCUCUAGGAUUGACCUAGGGGCUCUACAUACUCACCAUGCGCUUUAGGUAAAUGUUAGGAUCAGGCAAAUAGAGAAAUAUUGCCGAGGAAGAAAAUGGAGAAGUAAUUUUGGUAAUCAAAGAUUACCAAAAACUGUUAUAGAAAUUGUAAACCUAGAAUCAAGGUUUCAGAAUGGAAAAUGGCUCCAAAUCUGCAAUAGAACUUUAAAAAACAGUAAGAAUUAAUGUUUUCCUAAGUGACCAGAGAACUCUACCUUAAACUGGAUUUUAAAAUAGUGUUUACUGCUGUUCAUCCCAAAAACUUAGUGUAGGGGUCACCUUCCUCAGGAAACUUUUUCUACUCUGAUUUAGAGGCCCCUCCUGCGUUUCUAUAGCAUCCUCUGCAGACUCUUUCAAAGUAUUUAUUAUCCUGCAUCAUAAUUGUGGGUUGUAUUAGCCUGUACGCUUGUGGUUGUAGAGAAUGUGUCUGUCAUUUCCAAAACUAUCCCAGUGUCUAAACAUAAUAUGUUUUACCUAGUUUUUUAUUUUGCAUAUAUUUGUUAAGGAAAAGAAAUUAACUUUUCUAAUGAACUGAUUUAAAAAGAAAAAUGAAUCUAUUCAUAAAAGGAAAUCCGAGUCCUCGUAAGAAAAUUCUCAAAUCAAAAGCAUAAGGAAAACCUGUUUCCUGAAUUCACUGGGGCUGAAUUAUGUAUCGUUGUGUUCUGUUCUUUACACAUGCAUUUGUCUUCCUGUAUAGAGACUCAUUUGUGUUGAGUUGAUAUAGUUUAAAGACUAGAGGCUCAUUCAAGUUACCUCAGGUAAUGGGACUCCAGAAAGUAAUAUUACUUCAAGUAAUGUGGGACUCCAGAAAGCUACACAUUCAGGAAUCAUAGGACCUAGAGGGUGUUCUGAGACCAAGGUAGCUGUAAGGUCCAUAAAAAUCAGAAUUUCUUUAAAACUUAUGAAUUGUUUAUUAUUGAAAUUUUUCAUUUAAUUUUUCUGGACCACAGUUGACAAUUGGUAACCAAAACCCUGGAAAAGGGGCCUACUGUAAAUAUUUUUCUGAUGAGGUCGCUUUACUUACAAUAGAAAUAAAACUUUAAACAAGGUAAAGAAAAAAAUGAGAAAUGCUAAUAUUAAUCUUGCCUUAGUGCUUUAUUUUGAACCCAACAGAUGCUUUUCACAUGUCUAACUUUCUCUUUUCUGUACUCCUGACUAAAUUAAUAUUCCUUCAAAAAAAGUGCUGCUUGUUUACGGUUUCUGCAGUAGUUAAUUAAUCUUACAAAUGGCCCAAUAUGAAUGCAUCAGAUAUUCUCCAUAUCAAGAUUCAGCUCCAGUUCUAACUGCUGACUGCCUCGUCCGCUGGAUUCUCAGGUCGAAUUUCCAAGCAAGGGAAUCCACUUGCUUCAGCUCACCUUUCUGAGUCAGCCCAUAUCAGUCCUGGCCUUCUGUGAAAUGUCCAUUCUUGGUUCAUAUCCCCACAUGCCCCCCACUUCUAAACUAUGACUGAGCAACGGCUACCUGAGAACCAUCCUUCCAGCAAAGGCUUGCAAAGGCAGGUGCGAUGGCAGCUAUCUAUCUUGAUCUGAAUCCUGUGAGAACAGUCAUUAUGGUUUCUAGCCAAUCCCACAGAUUUGGGAGUAAACUGAACCUCUUUGGAGAGGCUCAAAAGAUUCAUUUUGAAGCUUGCAAAGUCUAAGUAGAAUAAGUAGCUCUCUUAGAUGGGACCAGCUAAUUUUAUCAUUUUAUUAUAUGUAUUGCUCCAUACCCACUUGGAAUGCAAGUUCCAAUAGGCAUUUAUAUCUUGUGUUUUGUUUACUCUAAACCUCAACACUAGGAAGAGUUAUGGCAUUAUAAGGUACUUAAAAAAUAUUUUAUAAAUGAAUGAAUGAACUUAAAUGUCCAAAAGGGAGCAGCGGAGUGGCCAGUAGCAAAAUAAAUUAUGUUCACCCUUAUGUAAUAAAAUACAUUAUGUAAUAAAAUACGCUAUAUAAUAAGGUACAUUCAGGCAUUUAAAACAUGUUGUGUAAUAAGUUUGGCUGGGUGUGGUGGCUCAUGCCUUUAAUACCAGCACUUUGGGAUGCCAAAGCGGGUGGAUCACCUGAGUUCAGGAGUUCCCUGACCAGCCUGGCCAACACUGUGAAACCCAGUCUAUACUAAAAAUACAAAAAUUAGCCGGGCGUGGUGGUGCAUGCCUGUAAUCCCAGCUACUUGGGAGGCUGAGGCAGGAGAAUUGCUUGAACCCGGGAGGCGGAGGUUGCAGUGAGCCGAAAUCGCACCACUGCACUCCAGCCUGGGCGACAGAGAGAGACUCCAUCUAAAAUAAUAAUAAUAAUAAUAAUUUUAAUGACGUGAAAUAUUCAUGAUCUUCUCAAUGGGAAAAGUAAAUUACAAGAAAAUGAGAUAUGAGUAUGGAAAUAAACUAGAAAGAACUCAGCAGAUUGUUAGCAGUAGUUAUCCUAGAUCACACAAUUGAAGAUGAUUUCCAUUAUCUUCCUCUAAUUUUUAUAAAAUAUCUAUAGUGAACACCUAUUAGUGUUAUAACCAGAAACUUCAUACACAUGUACACACACAGAGACACAACACACACAGAGUUACACAAUAAAUGCUACACUAAAAAUAAUAAUAAUCACUUAAUAGUGAUGUACAUAAAAUGGAAUUAUUUUGUGUUGUUGGUAUAUCAGGAAUAGAAUUUCUAUUUACUCAGUUCCAAUUGUUCUGUAUCUGUAAGUCACAUAUGUUGCCUAACACCUGCCCCACAGUGUGAUUAUUUGUGUGUGCAUCUUUUCUACUGUAUAAUGGGGCAUUCUUAUUACAGAGGUAAUCUGUGUGUGUUUCAUCUUUGUGCUUUCCAUUGUGUCUAGAUCAAUGUUUGAAUCUAAUAAGAGGUUGCUAAAUGUAUUUUAAUGAUUGACUAAACGCAUGAAGAGUUAUAUUUCAGGGGCAUGACUUGCUUUAAGGUAUAUCCAAAUGUGAAUAGCAAGCCUAGUUUUAAUAAAACUACAUUUGGCAGAGUCUCUGCUUGCAAGUAAAUGAAAUUUAGACUUCAGAAAAUGUUUGAAUGGCCCUAAAUCUUUAGCAGGUUUUCAUAAGUGAUGAUGAAAUUUACCUGACACAGAACAAAGGACUAUUAAACUGGAAAAGACCAGGAAGGUUAUCUAUCAAUCUUUUAAUUUUUGAUGGAGAACUAGAAUUCCAAAAAGAUUAUUUAGUUCACUGCAGGUCACUUCUAUAGUAUUCCGACCAGAACUCUGUUCUUCCUGACUCUCAGUUCACCACUUCACCCGCUACAACACACUGUUUCUGCACGCCUGGCUAAAUUGGUCUUGACGUGAUGUACAUUCCUUCUUAAUAUGAGUCAGUGACCUGGUACUGGGAAAAUCUGUGAGUGGUUUAACAUGUCAGGCUAUUGUCUAAGAAAAAGCAAACCAUCUCCAUGUAGGGUUAAAAAGCAAAAAAAUAGUGCUUUUGAGAAAAGCUGUAAUAAGCACUUGCAGUUAAGGAAAAAUGUCUAAUGUACUUUUAAAGAACUACGAAUAAAGAACUAUGUUCUCUUUAUCUUAAUACAUUGUAUUGAUAUUACUUAUAAAAUGGUAAGACUUUUAAAUUUAUAAAGCCAAAACAUUUUAUUUCAUCUUUUUGCUAUCCUCCAUAUUAGCCCUAUUUUUCUAUUAUUAAUGUUCUUCAUCACUAACUGUGGUGUUAGAUACAGCAGGUCCUUAAAUAAUGUUGUUUCAUUUAAUAUCAUUUAGUUAUAAUGUUGAUAAGGAAAACAUCAGUUCCCAUCCAGGGCCAAUCUGUGUGUAGUUUGCACAUUCACCCCAUGUCUAUGUGGGUUUUCUCCUGAUACUCUGGUUUCUUCCUACAUCCCAAAAAUGUGCACAUCAGGUUAAUUGUCCUGUAUAAAUUGUGAUGGAAUACCAUAUUGUCCAGGGUUGGUUCUUGCCUUGUGCCCUGAACUGCCAGGAUAGGCCCUGGCCCCCAAGCAAUCCUAAACUGGAAUAACUGGGUAAAUGAUUAUCUUACUUGUUUUUAUUACUCUUUCCUAAAUAUAUGUAGAGCUAACAUUUAUUUCAAUGUUUAAUAUUAAAGUUCUUUGGUUCCUAUUUAGAAGCUGGGUGAUGUUUUGGGGGCCAGAAAUAUGUCAUAGGAAAUUAACUCUUGUUUAGAUUAUUUAACCAAUGGUAAAAUUGGUUUUGUUAUAUGUCAUUUGGUUUACAGUUUCAGUUUCCAAGAACCUACCAAUAACAUUAAGUGAGAACUUACUGUAAUUACUUGUCACUCUGAGAUUAAGAAAACCACAAGAAAGCAUGAUUAAGUUGUGCUUUUUAUUUGACCUCCAUAGUUAAGAAAAAUAGGAGUUUUUGGAAUGGAUAUUAUCUUAAAAUGUAAGAAAAUAGAUAUUAAGUUGGAGAAAUGAAUAUUAUGUUAUUCUUUGUUCAAUCCUUUGAUAGUUUCCCAUAGCAAUCAAUGACACCCAGUAGCAAAGAUUUUAAUUCCUACAUACUAAAUACAAAGUGCUCAGAUUUUAAUUCCUAAAUACUAUUUCUAGCAUUCAGGAUAGACAGAAAAUUUCUUCACUUGAAAAAAAUCAAAUCUGGCUCCUGUCCACUUUUCUCAUCCUUUUUUUCAAUAAUUUCUUAUAUGCACCUUUCACUCCACCCAUACAGAAUAAUUCAUAGUACCUUGAACAAAACUUUGUACUAUCUCACUCUAUGUCUUAAAGUGCUAUCACCUCAAGCUGGAAUGCCCUCCUGCAAAUUUGAACUCAUACAUCAUUUUUUUAAAGAAGACAUCCCCAACCCUCCAGCUUGAUUUCUAAGGUUUCUCCUCUGUGUUCUCAUGGUACUCAGGCAUAACCCAAUUAUAAUUUGCCUACAGUCCUAUAAUCAAUUAUCUUUACCUUCCAGUAAUUUUUGACUUCCUUGAUGGAAGACAUCAUGCCUUAUUCUAUUUUACAUUCACAGUACACUGCAAAAGUUUUGGCACAUAGUAGGUUCUAAAUAAAAGACAAUGUGUUUCCCAUGACUUCCCAUGACUACAUACAUACUAUCUUUGGAAUUUGAAAGAAAUUUGGUUGCCUUGGAAGUACCUCACCACAGAAUUCACUUGAUUACAGAGGGUUUGAGUAACUGGUUUUUAUUGUCUCCCAACAUGGCAUUUUAUUGAAGUCAUUGAGUUUAUGAGAAUAUGCUCAGUUUCACUCAUAAUAAGAAAAAUGCAAAGUAAGAUUAUAUUGAGACACUAUUUCUUACCUACCAGAUUAACAAAAAUUCAAAUGAUUGCUAAGAUAUUCUGUUAGCAAGUCUGUGGGAAAACAGGUACUCUCAUACAUCCUAGUGCGUGAGCAAAUGGUACAACCCUAAUGGAAGAAAUUUAACAACAUCUAACAAAUCUACAUAGCACUUGCUCUUUGCUGCAGAAAUUCUACCUUUAGGACUCUACCUUAAAGAAGGAAUUACCACAAAGUCAAUUUUUUAAUGAACAAUCUGAGUGCAAACCAUUUUUUCAGUUAUUCAUUACCGGAUUAUUUGUACAUCAAAUAGUGGGAACAACCUAAACAUCCAUCCAUAAGAGACUAGUUAAAAAAAUCUGUGGUAUAGCCAUACAAGAGACUACUAUACAAAUAAAAUUAAGAAGAUUUUGAUGUGCUAUGAUUUCCACAAUACAUUAAGGGAGGAAAAAGUGGGCAAUCUGAAUACAUAUUGAUAUUUACCUACUUGUACGAAAAGAAAUACAGGAAAAACACACCAAAAAUAAUAAAAGUGUUUUGUUAAUUAUUAAUAGAAAUUUUAAAAAUUUAAAUUAUUAAUAAAAAGAAAACUACAUUUAAAAUGGGGGGAUGGUGGGAUGAGAGCAGAAAAGUAAGGGGGUGAGUGGGAGAAACACUUCACUACGUACAUUUUUUACACAGUUUUGUUUUUGUUUUUUUUUUUUUUUGAGACAGAGUCUCACUCUGUUACCAAGGCUGGAGUGCAGUGGCGUGAUCUCAGCUCACUGCCUCCGCCUCCCAGGUAGCAGCGAUUCUCCUGCCUCAGCCUCCCGAGUAGUUAGGACUACAGGUAGGUGCCACCAUGCCCGGCUAAUUUUUUGUAUUUUUAGUAGAGACAGGGUCUCACUGUGUUAGCCAGGAUGGUCUCGAUCUCCUGACCUCAUGAUCCACCCACCUCAACCUCCUAAAGUGCUGGGAUUGCAGGCAUGAGCCACCUAGCCCAGCCUAUAGCUUUGAUUUUGAACCAUGAAAUGUUUUACAUAUAGUCAAAAUAAUAAAUGAAAAGGAUGAGGGAGAGAUAAGCAAACCUGAAAAUUGAAGACAAAUGAACAAAUAAACCUAACAUGGAUGUGUAUGUAAUAUAUUACACAAAAUAAUUAAUUAAAAUAAUUUUGAGUACAGUAUUCUAACUGCAUACGUUUAGUGAAAUAUAGGACAAAAGUCUGCAUGGAAAAUAUAAACUUUAUUAAUAAAUUUUUGUUGAAUUAUGAAACAUUUCUCAUGUAUUGUCAGAUAGAAAAAAAUAAAUGAAUAUAUUGAUGCUGUUGGGAACUGAGUUUUCGCCAUAAAACGAAUAAAAAUAUGGAAAGAAGGAUAAUAAGAGAGAAUUAGAGUAUUUAAAUUUGAAAUGAGGAGAUUAAUAAGAACUUAAGGUUUCCUACCUCUAUCUAGAAUCAAUGACACUUAGUAGCAAAGAGCUCAGCUAGUGCUCAAAUUUUAAUUUCUAAAUACUAUUUCUCCCCAAAAGUAAGUGGGCUUUUUGGAGAAAAGGCUAAAUUCAAGUCAGAUACAUGGAAAGUACAAAUUGAGUCUGGAACACCUUGUACCAGAAAAAAGGGAAACAGUCACUCAAAGACUAACAAGCUUGUAUUAAACAGGACAGAAAUCAGCUAAAAGUGCUCUUGAUAUGAGAUAAUUUUAGCAUGAAAAAAAUGGAGGUUAUAGACAUACUCAAAGUAUGAAAAAAGAAGGAGAGUUCUUCUGUAGAAAAGACACCAGUGCCAGCUGAUGAAUUCAGGUAGAAUGAUGGAAUUCAAAGAUCAUCAUUUUGCAGACACCAAUGAAAACAAUUGAUUGAAAAAAGAAACAUCAAUAGUUGCUGAAACUUUUGGGUGAAAGAUUACACAGCCUUAAGGUUUAAUUCCAUAGAUUACUUAUUAAUUACAAAGAGAAAAAUCAUUCUUCACAAUAGAGAAAUCUGACAGUUUCUUACUGUACCCAAGUGAUCAGACUUAACAUCACCAAAGGUGGAGUAACUUAACAAGAUAAGCUGAUAUUAUGCACCUCCUGUGAUUCAAUACAAAAUAAAGUAGGGUGACAUCAGCAAAAUGAUGAAAUAGAAAGUCCCAUAUCCUCCUUCCUUCCAUAGAGUCAUCAACUGAACAACAAUACAUGAAUUAAUUCCCUUUGUGAAAAAUCCAGAAACAAAUUAAGACACUGCUGGACCCCAGGCAAGCGCAAAACCAGCUGCAUAGAGGCCAGUAAAAAAAUUCACAACACUCACUUGCCAUAGUCCCUUUCACUGACUCAGCAGAGAGCAACUGGAAGAAAACUCCCAGCUUCUAGCUUCUCCCACAGUCCCAUAGGAGGAAAAGAUUUGGCUUGUACAUUUUUGUACAUUGAACAUUUAGGCUUUUGGCAGGGGACAGAGGGGCAGAAGGGUGGGUGGAUGGUUGCCCGAGAAACUAGUUUUUAUCUUAUCUGUCUCCAAGUGCUGACAGGACCCAAUAUAUUCUAGAAGCCAGGGGCUGCUGACAACAAAAGACAGCUUGGCAGCUUAUAGCAGCUCCAGAGAACACCAGAAGGAGUAAUAGAUUACAAGGUCUUGGAAGAAAAUCAACCAGUAAAUCCCUCUAAUUGAGAAUUUACACACACAAGUCUAUUGCAGAUGUAUCCACAGACUAGAGGUGAGAGGACCUCAGAAUCUCUUACUUGGCUGAUUGGUGAAGGUUUGUUCCUAUACAAACCCUGUUUUUUACAGAGUGAGAGAGGAAGCUAUUUUUUGAAAUGCACAGACCACAACAAAAGGUAACAAGGCGCAUUAAGAAAAAGGAAAAUAUAGACCAAUCCAAGGAACAAAAUAAGUCUCCAGAAACCAACUUAAUGAAAUGGAGAGAUUAAAUUACCUGACGAGAAUUCAAAAUAAUCAUCAUAAAGAUGUUCAAUAAACUCAGGAGAAAAAUGGAUGAACAAAGUGAGAAUUUCAACAAAGAAAUAGAAAAUAUUAAAAAUGGAAUCAAAUAGAAAUCUCAGACCUGAAGAAUAAAAUAACUGAAGUGAAAAAAUCACUACCUAGUUUUAAUAGCAAACAUGAUUAAGCUGAAGAAAGAAUCAGGGAACUUGAAGACAGGUCAUUUGAAAUUGCCCAGGGAGCAAAAUAAAAUAAAACAAAAUAAACAGUGAAGAAAGUCUAAGGGACUUAGGAAACAACAUCAAGUUUGCAAAUAUUUGUAUUAUGGGAGUCUCAAAAAGAGAAGAAAGAGAGAACAAUGCAGAAAGCUUAUUCGAAGAAAUAAUGGCCAAAACUUCCCAAAUACGGAAAAGGAAGUAGAGAUCCAAGUUCAAGAAGGCCAACAAACUCCAACUAGGAAGAACUCAAAGAUAACCACACCAGAAAAGGUUAUAAUAAAAAUGCCAAAAUUCAAAGGAUGUUAAAAGCAGAAAAAGAAAACUGAUUCAUCACAUAAAAGGGAGCCUCCAUAACACUAUGAGGAGAUAUCUAGCAGAAACCUUUCAGGACAAAAUGGAGAAGGGAGAUAUAUUCAAAAUGCUGAAAGAAAAAAUAAUUGCCAACUGAGAAUACUAUAGCCUGCAAAAUUGUCCUUCAAUAAUGAAGGAGGAGCUUCUGCACAACAACAAAACUGUCAACAGAGUAAAUAGACAGCCUACAAAAUGGGAGAAAAUAUUUGCAAACUAUACAUCUGACAAAGGUCCAAUAGCCAGUAUCUAUAAGGAACUUAAACAAAUUUACAAGAAAAAAAAAAAACAACUUUAUUUAAAAAGUGAGCAAGGGACAUGAACAGACACUUUUCAAAAGAAGACAUACAUGUGGCCAAUAAGCAUAUUAAAAAAGCUCAGUAUCACUGAUCAUUAGAAAAAUGUAAAUCGCUUCAUUUCAUUCAUUUCAUCUUCCAUCACUAAUAUCCUUUCCUCCAGUUGAUCGCAUCGGCUCCUGAGGCUUCUGCAUUCUUCACGUAGUUCUCGAGCCUUGGCUUUCAGCUCCAUGAGCUCCUUUAAGCACUUCUCUGUAUUGGUUACUCUAGUUAUACAUUCGUCUAAAUUUUUUUCAAAGUUUUUAACUUCUUUGCCUUUGGUUUGAAUUUCCUCCUGUAGCUCGGAGUAGUUUGAUCGUCUGAAGCCUUCUUCUCUCAACUCGUCAAAGUCAUUCUCCGUCCAGCUUUGUUCCAUUGCUGGUGAGGAACUGCAUUCCUUUGGAGGAGGAGAGGUGCUCUGCUUUUUAGAGUUUCCAGUUUUUCUGCUCUGUUUUUCCCCCAUCUUCGUGGUUUUAUCUACUUUUGGUCUUUGAUGAUGGUGAUGUACAGAUGGGUUUUUGGUGUGGAUGUCCUUUCUGUUUGUUAGUUUUCCUUCUAACAGACAGGACCCUCAGCUAGAGGUCUGUUGGAGUUUGCUAGAGGUCCACUCCAGACCCUGUUUGCCUGCGUAUCCACAGCGGCAGCUGCAGAACAGCAGAUUUUCGUGAACUGCGAAUGCUGCUGUCUGAUCAUUCCUCUGGAAGCUUUGUCUCAGAGGAGUACCCGGCCGUGUGAGGUGUCAGUCUGCCCCUACUGGGGGAUGCCUCCCAGUUAGGCUGCUCGGGGGUCAGGGUCAGGGACCCACUUGAGGAGGCAGUCUACCCAUUCUCAGAUAUCCAGCUGUGUGCUGGGAGAACCACUGCUCUCUUCAAAGCUGUCAGACAGGGACAUUUAAGUCUGCAGAGGUUACUGCUGUCUUUUUGUUUGUCUGUGCCCUGCCCCCAGAGGUGGAGUCUACAGAGGCAAGCAGGCCUCCUUGAGCUGUGGUGGGCUCCACCCAGUUCGAGUUUCCCAGAUGCUUUGUUUACCUAAGCAAGCCUGGGCGAUGGUGGGCGCCUAUCCCCCAGCCUCGCUGCCGCCUUGCAGUUUGAUCUCAGACUGCUUUGCUAGCAAUCAGCGAGACUCCAUGGGUGUAGGACCCUCCGAGCCAUGUGAGGGAUAUAAUCUCCUGGUGUGCCGUUUUUUAAGCCCGUCGGAAAAGUGCAGUAUUAGGGUGGGAGUGACCUGAUUUUCCAGGUGCCAUCUGUCAACCCUUUCUUUGACUAGGAAAGGGAACUCCCUGAUCCCUUGAGCUUCCCGAGUGAGGCAAUGCUUCACCCUGCUUCUGCUCACACACGGUGCACUGCACCCACUGUCCUGCGCCCACUGUCUGGCACUCCCUAGUGAGAUGAACCCGGUACCUCAGAUGAAAUGCAGAAAUCACCCGUCUUCUGCAUCGCUCACGCUGGGAGCUGUAGACCGGAGCUGUUCCUAUUCAGCCAUCUUGGGUAAAAUACCUAGGAACCCAGCUUACAAGGGACGCGAAGGACCUCUUCAAGGAGAACUACAAACCACUGCUCAGUGAAAUAAAAGAGGAUACAAAGAAAUGGAAGAACAUUCCAUGCUCAUGGGUAGGAAGAAUCAAUAUCAUGAAAAUGGCCAUACUGCCCAAGGUAAUUUACAGAUUCAAUGCCAUCCCCAUCAAGCUACCAAUGACUUUCUUCACAGAAUUGGAAAAAACUACUUUAAAGUUCAUAUGGAACCAAAAAAGAGCCCUCAUUGCCAAGUCAAUCCUAAGCCAAAGAACAAAGCUGGAGGCAUCACGCUACCUGACUUCAAACUAUACUACAAGGCUACAGUAACCAAAACAGCAUGGUACUGGUACCAAAACACAGAUAUAGAUCAAUGGAACAGAACAGAGCCCUCAGAAAUAAUGCUGCGUAUCUACAACUAUCUGAUCUUUGAAAAACCUGAGAAAAACAAGCAAUGGGGAAAGGAUUCCUUAUUUAAUAAAUGGUGCUGGGAAAACUGGCUAGCCAUAUGUAGAAAGCUGAAACUGGAUCCCUUCCUUACACCUUAUACAAAAAUCAAUUCAAGAUGGAUUAAAGACUUAAACAUUAGACCUAAAACCAUAAAAACCCUAGAAGAAAACCUAGGCAUUACCAUUCAGGACAUAGGCAUGGGAAAGGACUUCAUGUCUAAAACACCAAAAGCAAUGGCAACAAAAGACAAAAUUGACAAAUGGGAUCUAAUUAAACUAAAGAGCUUCUGCACAGCAAAAGAAACUACCAUCAGCGUGAACAGGCAACCUACAAAAUGGGAGAAAAUUUUCACAACCUACUCAUCUGACAAAGGGCUAAUAUCCAGAAUCUACAAUGAACUCAAACAAAUUUACAAGAAAAAAACAAACAACCCCAUCAAAAAGUGGGCAAAGGACAUGAACAGACACUUCUCAAAAGAAGACAUUUAUGCAGCCAAAAAACACAUGAAAAAAUGCUCACCAUCACUGGCCAUCAGAGAAAUGCAAAUCAAAACCACAAUGAGAUACCAUCUCACACCAGUUAGAAUGGCAGUCAUUCAAAAGUCAGGAAACAACAGGUGCUGGAGAGGAUGUGGAGAAAUUGGAACACUUCUACACUGUUGGUGGGACUGUAAACUAGUUCAACCAUUGUGGAAGUCAAUGUGGCAAUUCCUCAGGGAUCUAGAACUAGAAAUACCAUUUGACCCAGCCAUCCCAUUACUGGGUAUAUACCCAAAGGACUAUAAAUCAUGCUGCUAUAAAGACACAUGCACACAUAUGUUUACUGUGGCUCUGUUCACAAUAGCAAAGACUUGGAACCAACCCAAAUGUCCAAUAAUGAUAGACUGGAUUAAGAAAAUGUGGCACAUAUACACCAUGGAAUACUAUGCAGCCAUAAAAAAUGAUGAGUUCAUGUCCUUUGUAGGGACAUGGAUGAAAUUGGAAAUCAUCAUUCUCAGUAAACUAUCGCAAGAACAAAAAACCAAACACCGCAUAUUCUCACUCAUAGGUGGGAACUGAACAAUGAGAACACAUGGACACAGGAAGGGGAACAUUACACUCUGGGGACUGUUGUGGGGUCGGGGGAGAGGGGAGGGAUAGCAUGAGGAGAUAUACCUAAUGCUAAAUGAUGAGUUAAUGGGUGCAGCACACCAGCAUGGCACAUGUAUACAUAUGUAACUAACCUGCACAUUGUGAACAUAUACCCUAAAACUUAAAGUAUAAUAAUAAUAAAAUAAAAUAAAAUAAGAAAAAUGUAAAUCAAAACCACAGUGAGAUACAUACCAGUCAGAAUGGCUAUUACUAAAAAGUCAAAAAAUAACAGAUGCUGGUGAGGUUGCAGAGAAAAGGGAAUGCUUGUACACUGUUGGUGGUAAUGUAAAUUAGUUCAACCAUUGUGGAAAGCAGUUUGGCAAUUCCUCAAACACCUAAAGACAGAACUACCAUUUGAUCCAGCAAUCCCAUUACUAGAUACAUACCCAAAGGAAUAUAAAUUGUUCUAUCAUAAACACACAUGCAUAUGUUUGUUGCAGCACUAUUUACAAUAGCAGACAUGGAACCAGCCUAAAUGCCCAUCAGUGGUAGGCUGGAUAAAGAAAAUGUGGUACAUAUACACCAUGGAAUACAAUGCAGCCAUAGAAAGAACAAAAUCACAUCCUUUGCAAGAACAUGGAUGGAGCUAGAGGCCAUUAUCCUUAGCAAGCUACCACAGGAACAGAAAACCAAAUACCACAUGUUCUCACUUAUAAGUGGGAACUAAAUGAUGAGAACACAUGGACACAAAGAGGGGAACAACAGACACUUGGGCUGACCACAGGGUUGAGGCUGGGAGGAGGGAGAAGAACAGAAAAAAUAACUCUUGGGUACCAGUCUUGGGUACGUGGGUGAUGAAAUAAUCUGUACAUCUAACCGCUGUGACAUGAGAGUACCUAUAUAAGAAAGCUGCACGUGUAACCCUGAAUCUAAAAUUAAAAGUUAGAAGAAAUAAAGACCUAUAUAAGCAAAUACUGAGGGAGUUUAUUACCACUAUAUCGCCUUUACAAGAAAUGCUAAAAGGAGUCCUUCAAGUUGAAAUGAAAACACCCUAGGCAGCAGCAGAAAUUAUUAUGAGACCAUAAAGCUCACUGGUAAAGGUAAAUAUACAGAAAAAUAGAUAAUACUGUAAUAUUUUAGUGGCUGUGUAUAAAUCACCUUUAAUUCUGAUACUCAAGUUAAAAGGCAAAAGUAUAAAAAACACUAUAACUAUAUGACAAUAAUAAAAAGGGCAAGGGAGGUGAAAGAAUAGAGUUUUAUAUCCAAUUGAAGUUAAAGUUGUUAUCAGCUUAAAAUAUCAACUUUAUAUUUGUUACAACUAUAAGAUGUUUUAUGUAAGCCCCACAGUACCACAAAGAAAAUACUUUUUAAAAACUACCAAAUAAAUGAGAAAGAAAUCAAAGCCUAUCACUAUACAAAAAUCAACAAAACACAAAGGAAGACAGCAAGAGAAGAAAAGAUGGACAGAAAAGCCUCAAGACAAAACAAUUAACAAAAUGGUAAUAGUAAGUGCUUCCCUAUCAGUAGUUACAUUACAUGUAAAUAAAUUAAACUCCUCAAUCAAAAUGGAUAUAGUAGCUGAAUGGAUAACAAAAACAAGAUCCAGCUAUUGUUGUCUACAGAACACUAGCUUUAGAUUUAAAGACACUCACAGGCUGAAAGUGAAAGCAUGGAAAAUUUAUUCCAUCCAAAUGUUAACCGAGAGAGCAAAAGUAGCCAUAUUCAUAUCAGAAAAAAUGGACUUUAAGUCCAAAACUGUCACACAAAAAAAGAAGGACAUAAUCUAGUGAUUAAAAAGUCAAUUAACCAGGAAGAUAUAACAAUUAUAAAUAUAAACGCAUGCAAAUUCAAAGCACCCAAAUAUGUGUAAUAAUCAUUGAGAUAACUGAAGGGAGAAAUAGACAGUAACACAAUAAUAGUAGAAGAUAGCAUCCUACUUUCAACAAUAGAACACUUAGACCAAAAAUCAAUAAGAAAACAAUACUUGAACAACACUAUAGACCCAAUUGACCUGGCCAACUGAUACAGAACAUUUUACUCAACAGCAGCAGAAUGCACAUGCUUCUCAAACUCACACAAAAUACAUUCCAGGAUAGAUUACAUGUUGGAUCACAAAAUAAGUCUCUUUUCAGAACAUUGAUAUCAUACCAAGUAUCAAUUCCUACCACAGGGAAUGAAACUAAAAAUCAAUAGCAGAAGGAAAAAUGGGAAAUUAACAAAUAUGUGGAAAUUAAAUAAAACACUCUUCAAUAACAAUUUGGGUACAAGAAAAAAAUCAAAAGAGAAAUUUAAAAAUACCUUGAUAUAAGUAAAAACAAAACACCUACCAAAACUUAUGGAAUGCAACAAAAGCAGUAUUAUGAGGGAAGUUUAUAGUGAUAAAUGUCUACAUUUUUAAAAACAGAAAGAAUUAAAAUAAAUAGUUUAAUUCUACCUCAGGGAAACUCAAGAAACUAGAAAAAAAAGAGCAAACUAAACUCAAAAUUAGUAGAAAGGAAACAAUAAAGAUUAGAGCAAAAAUAAAUGAAAUAGAAAAUAUAAAAAUAAGAGAAAAAAUCAAUGAAAUUGGUUUUUUGAAAUGAUUAACAUCAUUGGCAAACCUUUAGUUACUAACAAAAAAGGAAGAAGACUCAAAUAAAUAAAAUUGGAAAUGAAAGAGAAGACAUUACAACUGAUCACUGGAAUAAAGAUGAUCAUAAUAGUCUAUAAUGUACAAUUAUACACUGAUAAAUUGGAAUAACCUAGAAAAAAUGGAUAUAUUUCUAAACACAUACAACCCCCAAGACUUCAUCUUGAAGAAAUAGAAAAUCUGAGCAGGCUUGUAACUAGUAAGGAGACUGAGUCACUAACCAAAAGCCUUCCAACAAAGAAACUUCCAGGAACAGAUGUCUUUACUGGUGACUUAUAUCAAACAUUUAAAGAACUAAUGCCAAUCCUUAUCAAACUCUCCAAAAAAACGGAAUAGAAGGGAACUCUUCCAAACUCAGUCUAUGAGGUCAGCAAUAGCCUGAUACCAAAGCCAGACAAAUAUACUAUGAGAAGAGAAACUAUAGGACAAUAUUCUUGAUGAACAUAGAUACAAAAAUCCUCAAAAAAAUAGUGCAAACUAAAUUCAACAGCACAUUAAAAGGUUAUACACCAUGACUAAGUGGCAUUGAUUCUUGGGAUGCAAGGAUGUUUCCACAUACAAAAAUCAGUUAAUGUAAUAUACCAAAAUAACAUAAUUAAGGAUAAAAAUGUUAUGAUCAUCCCAAUAGAUACAGAAAAAUUGUUUGACAAAAUGCAAUAUGAUUUCAUGAUAAAAACUUGCAACAAAGUAGGAAUAAAAGGAAAUUACCUCAACGUAAUAAAAGCCAUAUAUGAAAAACCCCACAAGUAACCUCAUUCUUCAUGGUAAAAACCUGAAAACUUGCGUGAGGAACAAGGCAAGGACUCCCACUGUGAUCAUUUCUAUUCAACAUUGUACUGGAAGUACUAGCCAUAGCAGUUAGGCAAGAAAAAAAAAAAGACAUCCAAAUUGUAAAUAAAAGAGUAAAAUUAUCUCUGUUUGGAAAUGACAUGAUCUUAUAUUUAGAAAACCCUAAAGAUUUCACACAGAAACAUACACACGCAGGCACACAUGCAUGCACACACACAAAAACAACUGUUAGAAUUAACAGUUCCAGGAUACAAAAUCAACAUACAAAAAUGAGUUAUGUUUCACUAACCACAAACUAUCCAAAAAGAAAAUUAAGAAAACAAUCCCAUUUAUAAUAGCAUAAAAAAGAAUAAAAUACAUAGAAAUAAACUGUCCCAAGUCAGUAAGCAACUUGUACACUGAAAACUGCAAAAUAUUCCCAAAAGAAAUUAAAGAAGAUACAAAUAAAUGGAAAGAUACUCCAUGGUCAUAGAUUGGAAGGUUAAUAUUAUUAAAAUGUCCAUACUACUCAAAGUAAUCUACAGAUUAAAUGCAAACCUCAUCAAAAUCCCAGUGGCAUUUUUUACCGAAAUAGAAAAAACAAUCCUAAAAUUCACAUGGAACCACAAAGGGCCCCAAAAAUCCAAAACAAUUUUGAGACAGGAGAACAAAGCUGGAAGCAUCCUACUUCCUGAUUUGAAAAUAUAUUACAAAGAUAUAGUAAUUAAAGCAGUAUGGUGAUGUUACAAAGAUAGACACAUAGACCAAUGGAACAGAAUACAGAGCCCAGAAAUAAAUCUAUGCAUAUGUUGUCAACUGACCUUUGACAAGGGCAUCAAGAAUACCCAAUGAGGAAAAGAUGGUCUCUUCCACAAAUGGGGUUGAGAAAACUGAAUAUUCACAUAUAAAAAAUUAAAAUGGACCCUUAUCAUACACCAUACACAAAAAUCUAUUUAAAAUGGAUUAAAGACUUAAAAGUAAGACCUGACACUGUAAAAUAUUCCAAUAAAAACAUAAAGGAAAAACUUCAUUACAUUAGUCUUGGCAAUGAUUCUUGAAUAUGACACCAAAAGCACAUGCCACAAAAGCAAAAAUAGACAAGUGGUGGAAUUACAUCAAAUUAAAAAGCUUCUGCACAUUAAAAAAAAUAAAAUAACCAACUGAGGGAAAAUGCAACCUAUGGAAUGGGAGAAAAUACCCUCAUAUUGUAUGUCUAAUAAGGAGUUAAUAUUCAAAAUAUAAAAGGAACUGCUACAACUCAAUAGCAAAAAACAAAAACAAAUAAUCCAAUUAGAAAGUAAACAAAGAACUUGAAUAGUCCUUUCUCCAAAGACGACAUGACCAACAGGCAUAUGAAAAGAAAUUAUAGGUCAAUGCUCCUGAUGAAUAUAGAUGUUUAAAAAAGUCACUAAUCAUCAAUUUUUAUAUAAAUUCAUAUAUAUAAAUAUAAGUAAGUGCUAGUGAGAAUGUAGAGAAAUUUACAUACAUACAAAAGUCACUAAUCUCAUAUAUAUACACACAAGUGCUAGUGAGAAUGUGGAGAAAUUAGAACUCUUGUACACAGUUGGUAAGAAUGUAAAAUGGUACGGCUGCUAUGGAAAACUAUGGAGGUUCCUCAAAAAAUUAAAAAUAGAACUACCAUAUGAUUCAACAAUUUGACUUCCGGGUAUACAUCCAAAAAAACUGAAAUUGGGAUCUUGAAGAGAUACAUGCACUCUCAUAUUCACUGCAGUAUUAUUCACACAGCCAAGAUGAGGAAACAACCUAAAUGUCCAUCAAUCGGCAAACGGGUAAAAAACGUAGUAUAUUCAUACAAUAAAACGUUAUUCAGCCUUGAAAAGAACAGGGAAAUCCUGCUAUGUGUGACAACAUGGAUCAACAUUGAGGACAUUAUGCUAAGUGAAAUAAGUCAGUCACAGAAGAACAAAUACUGCUUGAUUCCACUUAACAUGAGAUAUCUGAAACAGUCGAACUCAUAAAAGCAGAUAGUAGAUUUAUGAUUGCCAGGAGCUUGGGGAGGGUUCAAUGGAUAUAAAUUUUCAAUUAUGCAAGAUGAAUACCCUCUAGAGAUCCAGUGUACAACACACACACCUAUAAUUAACAAUACUGUACUGUAUAUUUAAAUUUUUAAGAGGGUAAAUUUCAUGUUAUAUUGUUGUAUUUUUUUACCACAAUUUUUAAAAAGAAAAAAAGAAAGAACUUUUAAAAUAUCUUUUUGUAUUCUUAAUCUAAUGAAGAAAUAAUCAGACAAAUGCAAACACUGAUAUAUUCUAUAAAACAAAUAGUCUGGACUUUUCUAAAAAGGACAAUAUAGUGUUUUUUAAAAAUAGGAAGAAAGAGGAUUAUUCUAGCUUAAAAGAAACUAAAAGGCAUAAUAAUGUAAUGUAAUUUAUAAGCCUAAGCUUUCAUUGGAUCUGGAAUUUUUAAAAAUAUACAUCUAUAAAAGUCACUUUUAAGUUAUUUUUUAGCCCCAAAAUAAAGAGGCUUAAAAAAACAUUAAUCAUUUUACAAUCUCUCAUGAUUUCUGUAGGUCAGAAAUCAGAAAAACCUGAAGUGGGCCGGGCACAGUGGCUCACGCCUGUAAUCCUAGCACUUUGUGAGGCUGAGGCAGGCGGAUCACCUGAGGUCAGGAGUUUGAAACUAGCCUGGCCAACAUGGCAAAACCCCGUCUUUACUAAAAAUAAAAGAAUUAGCCUGGCAUGGUGGCUGGUGCCUGUAAUCCCAGCUACUCAGGAGGCUGAGGCACAAGAAUCGCUUGAACCCAGGAGGCGGAGGUUGCAGUCAGCCAAGAUCAGGCCACUGCACUCCAGCCUGGGUGACAGAGCAAGACUCCAUCUCAAAAAAAAAAAAAAAAGAGAGCUGAACUGGGUGAUCCUGGCUCCAGGUUUCUCAUGAGGUUGCAGUCAGAUGGUAACUAGAGCUGGAAAACCAGGUGGCAGUGACUAGAGCAUCUGUGAGCUGGUGGGCAUCUCUUCAUGUAGUCCCAGGGCUUUUCCAUGUGAUCUUUACCGGGGGGCUUAUCUGGGUCUCUUCCCAGAACAAUCAGACAGCUUUAAGGCUCCAUCAAGUGUUGCAGCAAGUAAGGCAGAAGCAGAAUUGCCUUGGAUUCAGAAGUCACAGCAUCACUUUUGCUGUCACAAAAGCCUGCCCACAUUCAAACACAGAAUAAAUAAAUUAUCUCUCUUUAUAGGAGACUGACAACAUUCUGGAAGAAAGAGAAAUUGUGGUAGUCAUUUUUGGAAAAUAGAAUUUACCACAGACAACAAUGAGGCAGUUGGGGAAAUUUAAAUCUGGACUGUAUAAUAGAUGAUACUGAAUUAAUAACCAGUUUUCUUAGGUGUGAUGAUGAGAUUCAGUUAUAUAAAAAAUGUACUUAUUCUUACAUGAUACAUGCCAAAAGAUUUAAUGGCAGUGUCUUGAUAUCUGCAACUUGUUUUCAAAUGAUUCAGCAAAAUAAAAAAUAAAGAGAGAGACCGGGCACCAUGGCUCACGCCUGUAAUCCCAGCACUUUGGGAGGCAGACCCAGCACUUUGGGAGACAGAGGUCGGCAGAUCACGAGGUCAGGAGUUCGAGACCAGCCUGGCCAAUAUGGUGAAACCCCAUCUCUACUAAAAAUACAAAAAAUUAGCCAGGUUUGGUGGUGCACACCUGCAGUCCCAGCUACUUGGGAGGCUGAGGCAGAAGAAUCGCUUGAAUCCGGGUGGUGGAGAUUGCAGUGAGCCGAGAUCGCACCACUGCACUCCAGCCUGGGCGACAGAGUGAGACCCCAUCUCAAAAAAAGAAACAAAGAAAAAAUAAGUGUGGUGAACUGUAAGUAAUCAGAGAAUAGGUAAAGGUUACACAGAUGUUCACUCUACUAAUUAUUUGCCUUUUCUAUAGAUUUAGGAUAUUUUUCUCAAUUAAAUGAAGAGAAAGUAAAAUAUAAGUCAGAUAGCAUUAUUUUUCUGCUCACAACCCUCCAAUCUUCUCUCUUCGGAGUAGAAGGCAGGCUGCUUACCAAGGCCUGCAAGAUCCUGUGUGAUUCCCAAAGCUUACCUCUCUGAUUUCAUCUCCAGGCAAAGGAAACAGCAAGUACAAAACCCCCAUGAGUGUGCUUGGGGUGUUUUAGAAACAGCAAGUUGUUUACAAUUUCCUACUUUUAAUUGAUGUUUCAAAUAUCUUCUACUUAAACCUUUGUGUACACUUCUUAGAGAAUUCCUAUUUUGACCUCAAGUCCCUGCCUACUCAUUUCUUUCUUUGUAGUAGAAACUUCAGCCCUAAAAGAACUCAGUCAAAGCCAAAUCAUUUCUCACUACCCCCAAAAAGGCCUACAAAUUUGGGCCAGGAGAGGCAAUCCUGGCAAGGAAAUUUUUUUAAAAAGGUCCCAGUUACACUCAAAUUGGGAGUUUCACUAAAUUGAUAUCCCCCUUAGGAUGCUUAAUGCUCAGCUUCAAUCUUACCUCCAGGGCAUAUGAUAUUGUAUCAUAUCUGAGAUUUAGAUUGCUGAGGCAUUUCCUAUCAUAACUCAGUAGGUUCUUAAGAUUUUACUUUGCAGAGUUUAAUCCACUGGGGUUUUUUUGUCUGGUUGCUUAGGCUAAUGCUGCUUGGUGUUCUGAGCGACCUCACUUCCCUGUGGCCCUAGAGUGUGGGGUGACCUGUUGCAGAUGUUAGUAAUUUCCUAUCUUGGGUGGAGGCCCUCACAGAAGCUUUAUUUGCAUAUGAGUGUAUUUGCCCCUGAUGUUUUGGUCUUGGAUGUCAGCGGAAUUGUCCGUCCUUCUGAAGGUCAUACAAUACCGCUUUCCAGGGAGGUAUUAUAACACAGAUAAUUGAAUAAUUGGGCCCUCUCUGUUUUCCAAAAGGAGUGGGUUUGCCACAUCUUUUCUUGCAAACUAGCAAACCUAGGGUUAAGUAGGGCUUGUUGGUAAAUGUAGCGUGUCAGGAGCUCACAGCCAGAUAUGAGCCAGUAAGCAACGUAGGUGUCCUGGGAUGACAAAGGAGGAACAUACACACCUCAGUUGUCUUGCUGAUUCUACUCUGUGCUUCCAUGUCCCCUUCUGUAAAAAUGUCAAUAACACUACAAUAAUAAUAGAGGUCUCUCUUAUGAGAAAUUGGUUAUUUAGUAGACAUUAUAAAUCAAGGUUUCAAAAAGUAUUAUCGGGCCAUCUCAAUGUUCAUUGCAGUUGGCAUCAGUAAAGUGAACAUGGUCAAGGUGAUAUUCUCUAACCAUAGUAAAAUAAAGGGCUGAGGCAUUCAUUUGGUGUAAAUAGGACAAACACCAGGGAGGCUUGGCCAGGUGUCUUUUGUAGUAAAAUUGGGAUUCUGAGAUUGCUGUUUUCCAACUUGGCAACAGCCUUAAACAUCUUGGUAUCCUUUAAUGUUAUGAUUCCACUUCUAGGGAUGUCUCCUAAGGAAAGAGUGCUAAAUAGAGAAAAAGUGUAAAUUGUAAUGGCGACAGAAAAUAGAAACAACCUGAAUGUCCAACUGAAGGGAAAAUGUGUAAAUAAAUCAUAUUCACUUUAUAGAUGAUUGUACAGACUUAAAAAUUUAUGCUUAUGAAUAAUUUGGUGAUAACAUGAGGUAUGAGAGAUAUGUAUAAAAAGAAUACAAAAUUAUACAUAAAUGGCAAAGUUUUAAAACAAAAUGUCAUUAAAAUAACAAAAAGAUAUGGAUCUUUGAAUGUUGAGGAUUGGGCAUAUUUUUCUUUCUGCUCUUCCAUAUUUUUUAAUUUUUCUUUAAUGAUUUUAUGUCACUUUUUCUAACAAGAAGGAUAAAGCACUGAUUAAAAGUGCUAAGAUGAGUUCUUAGCAAAGAAUGAUUAUUCCUAUCUAAUUAUGUAUUAACAUUUAUAUGAAUCAUACUAACAUUAUAUGACUCAUUUUAAGAUAAUAUAUUAAGAGGUUCAUUAAAAUGAUACUUUUUGAGUAUAUAAGGAAUCUUUUUCUUCACAUUUCAAAACAUUAACUCUUUCUAAAAGUCCAUAGUGUGAGAGGUAAAACACUAAUAAUAUGUAAACUAUCAGCAAUUGUACUUCUCGCCAUAACAACUGUAUGGAUUGCAGACAAGAACAAGGAAAUAAAUAAGAAAGUCCCCUUGAGAAGGGAGAGAAGACAAAAGGAAUCUACUUUGUGCCAGGCAAUGUGCUACAUGCUUUCAUAAAUGACCUUAUUUAAUCCUCACAACAACUCUAUGAGGCAUAUAUAUGUGUGUGUGUGUGUGUGUGUAUAUAUAUAUAUGAUAAAAUAAGAUAUAUACACAUCUUAUUUUACCCUAGCAGCAAUUCUGUUAGAUGAGGAAACUGAAAAUUCUAAUAGAUGAAGAAACUGAGGUUCAAAGAAGUUGCAUAAUUGGACCAAAGGAAAACAACUAAGAAACAAGCCCACAUUCUUUCCACUGUCAUUGUGCUUUGUUGAUAGACUACCCCUGGCCCAUGCUCAUAGCCUUAGAUAGCCUCAUUUUUAAACAGAAUUUGGUCACACUUCUUAGUCUGGUUUCUUAUCCUAAGGGAUGUAGUAUACACAAACAUUAGAACAUGACAGAAAGAAGAGAAGGAAUGCUAGAGCAAUAGCAAUGGGGAAUGAAAGCUGACAAAAGAGUAAACCACCAAAACAAAAAAACAAAAACAAAACUCAACCCUAUUAAAAAGCAGCCCAGGAACUCAAAAAGCAUAGCUAUAUAGCAGUAUGGAACUAUUUUAUGACAGAAUAUACAACUCUAUGUCAUGCUGAGGUAAUCAUCAUAUUCAGUACUUUAUUUUCCAUAUACUCUGUAUGUACACACUCUGUAUACAGUAUGUAUAUGUAUUAGGGGGAAUGUAAUAUAUAAAAAUUUUUUGAACAAUGGGUAUUGCCACUCUUUCCUUUAAGGGUUCUGGCUUGAUGAAGUUUUGUUCAUUGGUUUGUCUUGCUUUGCUAUUGUAAUACAUAGAAUUCCAGUAGAAGAUCUACAAACACAAGCUGAUUCUUAAACUGAGAAAGCAAUAUCCAGAGUCAGAACUUGCUUUUUGCUUAUCUACCUAACUAAAAGCUGAAGAAUAAAUGAAGCAGUGACUGGUUAUUGAUACACUUUGCAACAUUUCACUAGAACAACUUAAAACUGGAAUUGAAGCAUCAACUGAAGAUUUCUGUGCAACUGUGGUUUAAAUUGAAUGCUGCGCUUUGUAUAAACAUAAUUUUUUGUGGUUUAACUUUAGGCUGUUCUCUGCGGUCUUCCCAUAUAAUGGGAAUGCGUCAGAAGCACAGCUUCGUUUCCUGUGUAGGCUGGAAACUGUUAACUGCAAAGUUUGGAGACAGUCUCAGAGAGCUCACUGCCAUAUGUUAAACUAAACUUGAUAUGAAAAAUCAUAUCAGUUUCCAGUUUCCCAGAACAUUAAAAAGAAAAAUAAAAAAGGAGCUCAAGCUUUAUAAAUAUAAAAAGCAUCUGUCUGCACAGGAAAUUCUACUCUGUUAUUUUGCAAAUGAUCCCUACUUAUAUUUACAAGAGAAAUCAGAUCUGAUGAACUAUAUGGAAGUAACACAUUAUUUUGUUCAAAAUUUUGAAAUAUAUAUUUAUAAUUCUGUACAGCUGGCUGGACUGUGAACUAACUAUCAUUGUACAGAGAUCUCAACAGUGCUGCCCAGCAUGAUCUUAAAGCAUGUAUGUUUCCAAGUGAAAGGUGAUGGAAUAUUUUGACAGCAUGCUGCUAACUUAAACAUUUUUGUUUAAUGUAAUUUUUGUGUCUAAGUGCUCCCAACCACCAUUUCCAAGACAAGAAGACUCAUGAGCAUUCAGAAAACAUUUGGCACUGUUUCAUUUUAAUUUUUUACUUCUCCUUGACUCUUUGAGCCUAGAAAGAAUUUUCUCUGUAGUUGCUCACCCAGGUACAAGUGUCCUUGAGUUAAUCUUCGGUAGCUCAUUUUAGAAUCCGACUGUGACUAAAGUUGGAUUCUGUGACUGCCUUCUUGCCUGCCUCUCCACUGUCACCUAUAAUUUUGUCAUUUCUUUUGCUCUGAACCAGCUUGCUAUGCUAAAAGCCAUCCCUUCCUUUCACAUUUUAUAAUCCUCAUAAGAUUAACAGCCAAAAUCCAUGACCAGAACUCUGACCACGUACAGUCUACAGAGGACUUCAUGCUACCUUGAUAAUACCCCGUAUUUUACCAGCAACCAUCUCUCAGACUUGACUAUAACCCUCUGGUGUACCUCAUCAAUUCAAUGCUCCAGUGUUUAUCCUUGAUUUCAUUGUUUUCUUGCCUCACAGAGGUACCUAGAGAUUUUUUCCAACAGAAUCUUUCUGCCUUUUUCACUUAAUAGCCUAUCUAUGCCAGUAUUCCCAAGUAAACUCCCUUUAACUGUAAAGCCAUUAAUUUUUUCUUCUGAUUUCUUCUUUUCUCUUUCCCACCUUUGUCUUGCCCAGUUUUUACUUAUUUUCAUUCCUCUAGUAACUUAGGCCUCCUCUUACUCUCAGUUCCUUUUAUUACCAUUAUUUUCUCUAAAAUCAGAUUAAUAUCAUAUAUUAAUAAUAAUUAGUCAUCCAUCACUAAGUAGUGCCCACAUUUACUAACUUCUCUGACUUAAAAGUUGCUGUCUUAUCUAUGUUCUUUUCUUUCCUAGACAACACUUUGGAAUAGUAUCUUUUCUCCCCCUACCUUAUCACAAGAAGAUUAAAAUGACUCUUCUAGUAACAAUUACACCUACCCUCUCUUAUCUCGCACACUGGGAGGCACACGCCAUGGGCCCUCCUUGAUAGAGGUGAAGCUAAACCAUAUCCUUGUGGCAACUUAUAAAAACCUCAAUUGUGUGGUUUGCCUCUGCCUGUUCCUGAGGGCAUGCAGACAUAACGAACUUCUCUCUCAGCCUGGACCUGUGCUGGAAAAGAGUUUGACGCCCACUAAAACAGGCAUUUCACUGUGAAUUAGAAAGCCUCUGGAGAAGAGACUUUAUGUAAAUGUGUGUUCUCAGUGUGGAAUUGUUCUUCCAUGUUUACAAUUGUUUGUGUGUCUUUUUCUCUGUGCCAAAUUUCAGGUGACUGGAGACUGAUUAGCUGGUCUGUGCUAUCCUUACUCCACUUUAGCCAACACAUUGCACAUUCUUACCUCCAAAGUGGCAAAAAAUGCAAAUGUGUAUCAUUAUGCUUUAUUAGCUUUAGUAAAAAGUUUGCCAUAUUAAAGGUUAAAAUUUUUGGCAAUUUUUUGUACUCCUCGAAUAUCUAAUUAUUUAGAUUAAAAUAAUUAUAUAAUUAUUCUAGUUACCUUUCUUGAAUUUAAGUCUUAAAAAAAACCCUGCAAGCAAACAUUUACCUAUGUAACAAACCUGCACAUCUUGCACAUGUACCCCAGAACUUAAAAUUUAAAAAAAAACCUGCAAGCAAACCUAUCCCCUACAUAUUUUCUCAUACUUCAUCCAUACAUUUAACAUUAUAAAUUCUUUUAACUGUUUCUUCUUAAAUUACUUUGCACUAUGCCUUCAUAACAUUAUAUGCAGAUAGAAAGUUGCAUAUUAUUAUGACCAAAGGUCAUUUAUUAUCUAACCUUUCAUCUUGGUGUUGAUGAUGGUCAGCUCAUUAAAUUGUUCUUCUCAACCUGGGAGAAUUAAGCCCUAAUGCUCUUAUGAAUCCAUUGCACGUGAUGAGUUCACUUCUCUAGCUUUGUACCCUUGUUGUGAGAAUUAUGAAAAUAGGCAGUUGAAUUAUUUUCUCCAUAAUGAUAUAGAGAAAUAAUAAUACAGAGAAUGUGGAAUGUUCUCAAAAACUGGUUAAGAAAGGCUACAUUAAGAAAUAUUUAUUAAACUUCUAAUAUGAGACACCCACUACACUAAUUGAUAGAACAAAAAAGCUUUGUAAGCCAUAACCCUUUCUCUUAAAGAAUUUACAUUUUACUUUAUGAGAUAUGAAAUAAUCUGAUGAAAGAUCUGGAAAAUAAUCAAUGGAAUUUGAGAUUGAAUUAUGCAGCAUCAACUUGAAAUUUGAAAGUAAAAAAAACUAUGUGAACUUCAUCAAUAAUAGAGGUCUUCAAGGAGAAGGUAGAUUUAAGUUGAAACCUUAAUUUAGAUUUAAAUGAAAAUUGAAAAUAGACAAUGAAUUAUCUAUGAAUUGUGAGGAAGUGAGGAGGCAUUCAGGACAAGGAAGAGGAAAGCCAUAAGACAGUAAUAAGCAAAUCAGGUGAUAGAACCAAGAGUCACAAGCAAAUCAUUUAAAUAAUCCAAAUAUCAAAUUUCUUAACUAUUAAAAAAAUAGGGAAAAUGUCAGUCUCACAGGGUUGUGGCAAAGAACAAGUUUGUGAAGAUAAUGUAUGUGAAGGUACUGGGAAAUAUAGAGACAGUAAGGGCUCCUGGUAAAUAGGAUAGGAUUCUUAGGAUAAAGACAGCUUAGGAAGGUUUUUGCCAUUUGCCUCUUUCUCAUUAAAAUGGCAUGCAGAUUAUUCAGCAUCCUCUAUGCUGUACAGCAUGAAUUAUUUCUAGAAGAUUAAUCACCAAAUCAAAUGCAAAAGCAUCCUUCUACCAAGUUUUUUCUUGUCUUUGAUGAAAUCACUGGGUUCACUGCUUUUAUCAGUUUUCAUUUGGAUAAUAUUUAAAAUGCUCUUUUAUCCCAAUUUGAAUACCCUCAAUCAAUGUCAGCCUCUUUUAAUUUGGUUUAAGAUUACAGGAAAACAUCAUGACCCUAUAGAUUUUUCCACCACAACUAUUAAGAACAAUGGAGCCAGACAUAUUUUAACAACAAAAGAACAUGAAUGGAGUUUGCCUUUUGACUUAUCAUUUAAGUCCUGGGUUUCAGAUCAUGAUAAAUAUUUCAGAAUGGGGUAAUCCUGGAUCAUGAUUAUAAAGUAUAUCAAGGCUGCAACACAAGUGCUGCUGGGAUUUUUUAAAGGGAAACAUUCUUAUGAGUCUUGAAGUCUCAAUGAAGAAUGGAAGAUUUGAAUGAGUUUUCCUGGAUGAUCAUGAUUCGGUUAGGUGAAGGAGUGGAGAAGGCAACAAUCUGCAGGAAGAAUAAUCCUGGAAUGUUUAGAAAAUCCAGGAGGGGCUUUACUGAAAUGGAAAUCUAAUACUGGAGAACAAUGAGAAAUAAAGUUGGAUAGUUACAGUUAAGUUGAAUGAGUAACUAAUUCAGUCACCACACACACCCUAUUUUAAUUUCUUAAGCAUAUUCUGAGGGUCUCAAGGACCCACAGGAAAAAAAAAAGCAUAAGUCCUUUUAAAAAUUGUAUUAUAUCUACGACAUCCAUAUAACAAGGCUGAAAUUAGAAUCUGGAUGUGUUAUUUUAAUAUUUUUAAUUGUGAUAAAAUACACAUAAUGUAAAAUUUAUCAUCUUAAUUAUUUUUAAGUACAGAACUCAGUAGUGUCAAGCACAUUCACAUUGUUGUGACACAGGUCUCCAAAACAUUUUCAUAUUGCAAAUCUGCAUCUCUAUAUCCAUCAAACAGCAAUUCCGUAUUCCUCCUGCCCCGAAUCCUUAGCAACUACUAUUCUGUUUUAUGUCUCUAUAAACUUGACUAUUCCAGGUACCUCACUUAAGUGGAACCAAACAGUAUUUUUCUUAUUGUUACUGGCUUAUUUCACUUAGCAUAAUAUCCUCAAGGUUCAUUGAUGUUAUCGCAUGUGUCAGAAUUUUCUUCCUUUUUAAGACUGAGUAAUAUUCCAUUGUAUGUAUAUAUCACAUUUGGUGUAUUCAUUCAUUCAUUGAUGAACACUUAAAUUGCUUCCACCUUGUGGCCAUUGUGAAUAAAAGCUGCAGUGAACAUGGGUGUA